AAUUGCAACUCCGGCUGGAGCCCCGGACCUGCAAGCCUGGGUGUCCGUGGGUCCGUCUGCCCAGCCAUCUGCUGGUGGCACCUCUCCCUCCUGCCGCCUCCCUCGGUGAACCCCACCUUGCAGAAGUGCAGCUCGCCCGGAGCAGCCCAGGAGCUCAGCAUGCGUCCCCCAGGCUUCAGGAACUUCUUGCUGCUGGCGUCCUCCCUUCUCUUUGCUGGGUUGUCAGCUGUUCCUCAAAGCUUCUCGCCAUCUCUGAGGCCAUGGUAAGUGUGACUGUGGCAAGUGCAAGUGUGACCAGGGAUGGUAUGGGGAUGCUUGCCAGUACCCAACUAACUGUGACUUGACAAAGAAGAAAAGUAACCAAAUGUGCAAGAAUUCACAAGACAUCAUCUGCUCUAAUGCAGGUACAUGUCACUGUGGCAGGUGUAAGUGUGAUAAUUCAGAUGGAAGUGGACUUGUGUAUGGUAAAUUUUGUGAGUGUGACGAUAGAGAAUGCAUAGACGAUGAAACAGAAGAAAUAUGUGGAGGCCAUGGGAAGUGUUACUGUGGAAACUGCUACUGCAAGGCUGGUUGGCAUGGAGAUAAAUGUGAAUUCCAGUGCGAUAUCACCCCCUGGGAAAGCAAGCGAAGAUGCACGUCUCCAGAUGGCAAAAUCUGCAGUAACAGAGGGACUUGUGUAUGUGGUGAAUGUACCUGUCACGAUGUUGAUCCGACUGGGGACUGGGGAGAUAUUCAUGGGGACACCUGUGAAUGUGAUGAGAGGGACUGUAGAGCUGUCUAUGACCGAUAUUCUGAUGACUUCUGUUCAGGUCAUGGACAGUGUAAUUGCGGAAGAUGUGACUGCAAAGCAGGCUGGUAUGGGAAGAAGUGUGAGCACCCACAGUCCUGCACGCUGUCAGCUGAGGAGAGCAUCAGGAAGUGCCAGGGAAGCUCGGAUCUGCCUUGCUCUGGGAGGGGUAAAUGUGAAUGUGGCAAAUGCACCUGCUAUCCUCCAGGAGAUCGCCGGGUGUAUGGCAAGACUUGUGAGUGUGAUGAUCGCCGCUGUGAAGACCUCGAUGGUGUGGUCUGUGGAGGCCACGGCACAUGUUCCUGUGGUCGCUGUGUUUGUGAGAGAGGAUGGUUUGGAAAGCUCUGCCAACAUCCGCGGAAGUGUAACAUGACGGAAGAACAAAGCAAGAAUCUGUGUGAAUCAGCAGAUGGCAUAUUGUGCUCGGGGAAGGGUUCUUGUCAUUGUGGGAAGUGCAUUUGUUCUGCUGAAGAGUGGUAUAUUUCUGGGGAGUUCUGUGACUGUGAUGACAGAGACUGCGACAAACAUGAUGGUCUCAUUUGUACAGGGAAUGGAAUAUGUAGCUGUGGAAACUGUGAAUGCUGGGAUGGAUGGAAUGGAAAUGCAUGUGAAAUCUGGCUUGGCUCAGAAUAUCCUUAACAAUUACAUGAGAGAGCAAUUUUGAUGACGUAUUCGCUGAUGCACAGACAUUGGAAUUCAUUACAUUAUCUAGCCAUCGUAAUACAAAUGACCUUUGGAUUUCUCUAUCACGGCGCUUAUCCUCCUAUUAAGGAUCAGAAAGUUAAACUUUACGGACCACGUACGUCCCUGUCUCAUAUUCUUCUUUGUUGGUUUCUGUUUAAUACUUUAAAGCUGUAAAAAAAAUUUAAAAAAUUCCUUCUGAGCUCCCAGGCCAUACAAAAGCAACUUAAGGGUGGAUUUGGCUGGCAGCUGGGCAGUACUUUGUCAGCCUCAGCUCCACUGGAACUGCCCUUGAUUCUCUAUAGCUCAUCACAAAACCUCAGGUAUGUCUUAUUUUUCUUAUAAUCCUCUGUAUGUUAUUAUCCUUUUUAUUAACAACAACAACUACAACAAAAGUGCUGCUCUUUUUCAUAGUCUCAUGUAAGAAGAGUGUCAAAAAUGUCCUCGGCAUUUGUUUUCUCAGAAAAAGAAUUUAGAUAUUGGAGAAAUUAUCAUACCAUAAAAAGUUCAAAAUGUGAUUCAUCUAAAAUUUUGGACAAAGAUGAAAAUAUAGUCAGCUCUGUUCUAGUGUUCAUUUAGUUAGAAACCAUAGUACCGGAACUGUAUUAUAGUAGAAGUUAAUGGUACCUAAACUCUAAGGAAUGCUUUUUCUUUGAAAACAGAAAUAUUUUUACUUAUUUCUGUCCACUAUGUUUGUGUGUAUGUGUGUGUUUGUGUGUGUAUGUGUGGUUUUGAUGCCAGCAAUGCAAACACCAAUAUAUCUAUUAAGAAGUGAUUGAAUUUAGAUUGGAAAAAAUAAAAUAGUUACAUGUAAAGACAUAAACUCUUUCCUUCUUAAAUGUGAUUUUCAACUCUAUGAUAGAAACUCCCUCUAAAAAACAAGCAGGGCAAGAACAAACUUACUUGUAAUGGGUGAGAGAAAAUAAGCAAAUCUCAUUGGCUCAUUCCUGUUUUUAGGAAGUUGCAGUGGGAUUAAUGUCAAUUGGAAGGGAUGCAGCAAGUUUAGAGAAGGUGUUGGCACUAACGCUGCUUGUUUGGCAAAUCAUCAUCACUGAGGUAUUCCACCCAGAGACUUUUUCAAAAAAGUCAACUAAAGUGCUAAGUCAUAAGAGGAGAGCCAUUAUACCCGUUGUCUUUCUGGGCUCCUUGAGUUUAUCUGGAUUCCAACAGCACUUGGAAAGUACCGCCCUCCACUACCUCAAAUGCAAACACAAUCUCUGCCAGUAGACAUUGGAAUUAGACUUAGUGAAAACCAGGAAAAAAAAAAAAAACUAAAAUAUAACUCAGCCUUAGUUUGCAGACUCAACUGUCAACACUUUGAAACCCUACUCCAUAUUCAAGAGAGUCAACAGGCCCUAUGUCACAUUGUAGGCUAAGAAACCUCAGCUAUGACUACUAUUUCACUCAAAGUAAGACCAUGUACAUCCUGGAUUUUGAUAUGCCUGCAUUUUGGAAAAAAAAAUUGAGGAUUUAGCCCAGUCGCUUUCCCUUGAUAUAGCCUUGUUCUGAAUUAAAAUGGAAAAAAUAUUUCAAUUAUUUUCAUCUUGUUCUCAACUGGAUGUUAGUCAAUGUGGUCUCUUUUUGAAUAUGUAUCAAAUAUUAAUGAUCCAUAAUAUUAGGGAGAUAAUUUUAAAUGAAGUGAUACGUGUCUAACUUACUUAAAGAAUAAGUUUUUGGUUUUUGCUUUUAAAGACAACCAAAUCUGAUAUUGUUCAUCCUGAUAAAAAUAACAACUUUUAGUGCUUAAAGCAUUAAUUAAGCAAGUGGCUAGGUAUGAUAAAGAACUUCUGCUUGCUCCCCAAGAGGCAAACUAUUAGAAGAACUGGAGCGGGAGUCCUUUGGACCCAUCGUGGAUCUCUUUAAGCCACUGCUACCCAAAAACAUUCAGGACAAGCAAACAUUUAGAGCAAGAAUCUCCAAAUUCUUCAGGAUUUGUAAUGAAAUGAUGUUCAGUUCCAUUUUGCUCUUUACAUAGGGUGGAGAAUUGUCAUGUCUUCUCUAAUUUUUCCAAGUAAAGUGGUAGCAAAAUGUUUUAAAAAGCAAUCUUAUAUUAGAAAACAAAAAUGUUGUCACUUGAAAUACCAAAACAACAUUUCUGAGCGUUGUUGAGGGACUGGCAAAGCAAUCAGCUACUAUAACAAAUCAGUAGAAAUAACCCUCCCACACCAGAUAUGCAUGCAGAAGGAAUGGAGUAUUAUAGAGACUUGAUACAAUGGACAUAUGCACAUGGAGGUACAAAACACACAGUCUAAAUACAAAUGAAUUCCAUCAGAUUUACUAUACGGAACAUCAGUAGUGACAGAUUGCACUUCUUACUUAAUAACAGCAAACUUAAUUUCUGAGGGGAAAAAAAUGGCGAAGUCUUAUCCCAAACAAAUAGCAAGAGAGGUAUCAUCAAAGAGCUAAAAUUUUCUUUGGCAUGGUAAAGGGGGAAAUUGAGUUUACCAACUUAUUUACAUGACAUUUCUCUAUAUUGGUGAGUAAUGCAAUGCCAUUUUGUUACAUAAAGUUGUUUGAUGUUUUUUAAUAUGCCUUCAUAUAAAUAUUUUAUUCAAUAUGUUGUAUUUGUGAAUUUAACAAAUGAUAUUAAACACAAACUACAAUGCAGACAGACAAACUCUUUGUAUGCAAAUUAGCAAUACAUACCAACAGUUCUUGAUACACAGGUACCUACUACAUGCAGCUCAUCAUUGCUGUCCUCUUCCCAUGCUACAGGUGAGACCAGACACAAAGUAAAUGACCUAACUCAAUUACAAAUAACAAGGACCCCUCUGCAAUAUGUCUAAACAUAUAUUAGAAGAAAGUAUUUGACAUCCUUCAUAGGGAUAAAUGCCCUUAUAGACACCCCAUAUAUAAAACACAACAGAGAUACACAUUUACAUAAAUCUCAGUCAUUUACAAAAAUAAAUCUUGUCUUAAUUUAAACCAAUAAACAGACUUGCAGGGGAAAAAGAAACCAGCAAGUAGGGCUAAUUAUCAGUAACAAAUAGAUGGGGGUGUUUGCUCUGUGUGUGUGUGUGUGUGUGUGUGUGUGUGUGUGUAUAUGUGUGUGUUUGUGUGAAGUGAAGUGUUGCUGCUGUAAGUAGUGUCCAUAAGCCCAUUUGACUGUAUUACAAGUUAGUUAAUUACUCAUAUAGUUGGCCACAUAUUAUGGGAUCUAUGUUUUCUGAAAAUAAUUGGUUAAUGGAAGUUAUCUAAUAUAUUUUAACUGUUCCUGUUAAAAACAAUAGGCUUCAAGAUGACAUAACACCAAAUCAAAAAUGACCAAAGGAAUCAUUUUGUUUGUUAGAUUUGUAAUUUAGCAUCAUUGGCAAUAAAUCUACUCAAACGUU